CCACUUGGCCAGAUAUGAGAGGACCUGAGUUCUAGUCCUAGGUCUGCUUCUUAUUAGACUUAGAGCAGGUCAACCUACUUACCAAUCUGUUUUCCUGUCUGUAAAAGGAGAUAAGAGGCCAGCCUGCCUCAGAGAUGUUGUGAGUUCAGGGCAAUGUUGCCUGAAGGCAACGUGUCUCAGACACCUCUGGAGAGGGCCUUGAUAGUGAACCCCAUCCCCUUAAGGGUCAUUGAGGUGGGUUGGGGAAUUCGGCCACAGGGGAUCAUUGAGGUGUCCACAUGGGGCUAUUAUAUUUGCAUCUGUGGGUAGUGGUGGAGAUAGAAAGUGGGCAAGAAACAGCAGAGUGGCCUGUCUCAGGGCACUGGGAGUGGGGUAUAAGUCUAGGAGAGAGAGGUGUGGCCUGCAUCAUGUUUUCUCCAAAGACAUGAAUGCUGGAGGCUGCUGAGGAGAAAAACCUUUCUUGUCUUGGGGUCAAGUGACAAGCAUUUAGUCCCAGCCCUGCCACUUAACCAUCUGUGUGAUUUGAGGCAAGUUGGCUGGAGUUCCGUAACCUCCAUUUUCUCAUAUGUAAAACAGGGCUAAUGAUUCCCAUGUUGCAGAGCAUGUGAAAGCAUCCUGUCCCUUUCCUGGUAUGCAGUGGACAUUGAUAAAUAGUGGUGAACUCUAGAUCACUUUAGUAUUUCCCGGGGUUAAUCCAAUAAGUCCCAAUUCUUUGCAGGAUUCCACAUUUCUCCCUUGCCUUUCAGACUCACUUAGGCACAUUGUAGUUGGAUGUGAAGGAAGGUCUGGCCAUAGAAUGAGACCCCCAUGAAUUAUUGAGGGGGAAGACCCUGUGCUUCCUGGAAGGAGAUGCUGAUCAGUGUUUUUCUGGUGGCUGCAGUGGGUACGCAGGGCCAUUUUGGAAGCGAGAAUGUUUGUCUUGCCAAGUACGAGAUUGAGUGUCACCGGUUUGCUUUCUGGGAAUAAUGGCUGUGCCGAUGAAAUAGAUUUAUGGCGCUGAGGUACGUCACAGAUGAGACUGAUUUUUUUUUCCCACUUUAAAUGUCGAUGUUUUCUAAUUAUUCAAAUAAUGUGCUUAUUUUAGAAUAUUGGGAAAGUAUCAAGAAAGAAAAAAAUGUCUACUUCUAAGUCCAGGGGUGAUUACUGCUAACGUUUUGGUAAAUUUCCCUUUCUUCUUUUUUCAAAUGCACAUAAGCUUUUUUUUUAAAUAUGCUUUAUGCACUUACGAUAUCAUGUGUAUUUCCCAGAUCAUUACAUAUUCCUUAAGAACAUUUUUAUUUGGUACAUAACAGUCUGUGGUGCACACAUGCCAUAAUAUUCUUAAUCAUUCCCUGUUCCAUAGUUAGGCAUUUAGAUUGCUUCUACUUUUCUCCUAAAAUACAUAAAAAUAUUUCACUUUUUAAAGAACGAUUUUCUUAAAUUCCUGGAACUGGGAUUCCUAGAUCAAAGAAUAAGCACAUUUAAAAGUGUAUUUUGGUGGACUCUUCUAUUUACCUUAUAUUAAAAAGCAAAAAAGUUAUGGUGUGGUGAGGCGGCUGCAGGCCAGCUUGGGUGAGGUCCCUGCUUCUGACCAUUGUGCACAGAAGGCUGCCUCCUUGCUGCUCACUUGCUUCCUGGCGGACAGUACAAUCAGCCUCUUGUGGUUUGCCAGUGAAAUUUAAGUACUGGGUCAGCCUUUCCAGUGCUUCUCUCUCUGUCAGGAAGUUCAUCUGUGAAUCUAACCUAAAUCUCAUCUGCUGCAUUUUAAAUCCUCACCUGCUGUCGCUUCCCCUCAGUGGAGUGGAACAGAGCAAAGCUGCGCACUGUCUGCAGGCAGCCUUGUUCACCUCUCUCCCGUGACCACUGCGACGCCAGCUGCCAGCCUUAUGUUACCCUGGAGGAAAUUUGAGGGUCUCUGGCUACUGCUGUCGAGACUGGGAGGGCAGUCCUUGCAUCGAGUUGCUGCUGAUAACACCAGCCAUAACCAGCAGACCACAGCAUUCAGGCAUCCUGUGACGGGACAGUUUUCUCCAGAAAAUAGUGAAUUCAUUCUUCAAGAAGAGCCGAAUCCACAUAUGUCGAAGCAAGACAGAAACCAAAGACCGUCCAGCAUGGUCAGUGAAACAUCCACGGCUGGGACCGCCUCCACCCUGGAGGCCAAGCCUGGACCCAAGAUCAUAAAGUCCAGCAGUAAAGUCCACAGCUUUGGGAAGAGAGACCAGGCCAUUCGGAGGAACCCCAAUGUUCCCGUGGUGGUGAGGGGCUGGCUGCACAAGCAGGACAGUUCUGGGAUGAGGCUGUGGAAAAGGAGGUGGUUUGUGCUUGCUGAUUACUGCUUAUUUUACUAUAAAGACAGCCGAGAAGAAGCGGUCCUCGGGAGCAUCCCCUUGCCCAGCUACGUGAUCUCUCCUGUGGCCCCUGAGGAUCGCAUAAGCCGCAAAUAUUCCUUUAAGGCUGUGCACACGGGGAUGCGAGCGCUCAUCUAUAACAGCUCCACAGCGGGCUCUCAGGCCGAGCAGUCAGGCAUGAGGACCUACUACUUCAGUGCCGACACCCAGGAGGACAUGAACGCUUGGGUCAGGGCCAUGAACCAGGCUGCACAGGUGCUGUCUCGAUCGUCACUGAAGAGGGAUAUGGAGAAGGUGGAGCGGCAGGCUGUCCCCCAGGCCAACCACACAGAGUCCUGUCACGAAUGUGGCCGGGUGGGACCCGGACAUACGAGAGAUUGUCCUCAUCGUGGCCAUGAUGACAUUGUCAACUUCGAGAGGCAGGAGCAGGAGGGAGAGCAGUACCGUUCCCAGAGGGACCCACUGGAGGGCAAGCGGGACCGGAGCAAGGCCAGGUCUCCGUACUCGCCAGCCGAGGAGGAUGCCUUGUUUAUGGAUUUACCCACUGGCCCAAGAGGCCAGCAGGCACAGCCCCAACGGGCAGAGAAGAAUGGAAUGCUGCCUGCCUCAUAUGGCCCAGGAGAACAGAAUGGGACUGGUGGGUACCAGCGGGCCUUUCCUCCCAGGACCAACCCUGAAAAACACAGCCAAAGGAAGAGCAAUCUGGCCCAGGUGGAGCACUGGGCAAGGGCCCAGAAAGGGGAUAGCAGGAGUCUUCCCUUGGACCAGACGCUUCCUCGCCAGGGUCCUGGCCAAUCCCUGUCCUUCCCAGAAAACUACCAGACUCUUCCCAAGAGCACCCGACACCCCUCGGGGGGCUCCUCGCCACCUCCCCGAAACCUGCCAAGUGACUACAAGUAUGCGCAGGACCGAGCCAGCCACCUGAAGAUGUCGAGUGAAGAGCGCCGGGCGCACCGGGAUGGCACCGUGUGGCAGCUCUACGAGUGGCAGCAGCGCCAGCAGUUCCGGCACGGCAGCCCCACAGCGCCCAUCUGCCUUGGCUCCCCAGAGUUCACCGACCAGGGCCGGAGCAGGAGCAUGCUAGAGGUGCCCCGCUCCAUCUCUGUGCCUCCAUCUCCCUCGGACAUCCCUCCCCCAGGACCCCCAAGGGUCUUCCCACCCCGGCGGCCACACACACCAGCAGAGCGAGUCACAGUGAAGCCACCGGACCAGAGGAGGAGUGUGGACAUCUCGCUGGGGGAUUCUCCAAGGAGGGCACGGGGCCACGCUGUCAAGAACUCAUCUCAUGUGGACCGACGCUCCAUGCCCUCCAUGGGUUACAUGACCCACACCGUCAGCGCUCCCAGUUUACAUGGAAAAUCGCUGGAGGAGCUCUCGUUGCUUCUCACCCGGUUAAGGCGGCACCAGGCCAAGUUGGCCAGUGUGCGAAAUUUCGCCAUCAGCCAGUUACUGCAGCACCAGCUGACCUUUCCCACCUGCCAGGCUGAUGAUACCUACCUCCAGCUGAAGAAAGACCUGGAGUACCUGGAUCUAAAGAUUAAAAAUAAUGAACCUUUGAUCAACGUGCUUUACAAAGUGCUGAAGAAGUCAGCACGGGGCUGUCGGCCCAGGAGAAGCAUGACAGGCCGGGACCUUCUCAAGGAUCGAAGUCUGAAGCCUGUGAAGAUCGCUGAGAGCGACACUGACGUCAAACUGAGCAUCUUCUGUGAACAAGACAGGGUCCUCCAGGACUUGGAAGACAAGAUACGAGCCCUUAAAGAGAACAAAGACCAGCUAGAAUCUGUGCUGGAGGUGUUGCACAGACAGAUGGAGCAGUACCGAGACCAGCCCCAGCACUUGGAGAAGAUUGCCUACCAGCAGAAGUUGCUGCAGGAGGACCUUGUCCAUAUCCGAGCUGAGCUCUCCAGAGAGUCCACUGAGAUGGAAAAUGCUUGGAACGAAUACCUGAAGUUGGAGAAUGAUGUGGAACAGCUGAAGCAGACCCUGCAGGAGCAACACAGAAGAGCCUUUUUUUUCCAGGAGAAAUCGCAGAUACAGAAAGAUCUAUGGAGAAUUGAAGAUGUCACUGCAGGCCUGAGUGCAAAUAAAGAGAACUUCAGAAUUCUAGUGGAGUCAGUAAAAAAUCCGGAGAGAAAAACGGUGCCUUUGUUUCCUCACCCGCCUGUGCCUUCACUCUCAACUUCUGAGAGCAAGCCGCCCCCACAGCCCAGUCCUCCCACCAGCCCUGUGCGGACCCCUCUGGAGGUUCGACUCUUCCCCCAGCUGCAAACCUACGUGCCGUACCGACCUCACCCACCCCAGCUGAGGAAAGUGACAUCCCCCCUUCAGUCACCAACUAAGGCGAAGCCCAAAGUUCAGGAAGAUGAAGCACCUCCCAGGCCCCCACUCCCCGAACUCUACAGCCCAGAGGACCAGCCCCCGGCUGUGCCGCCUCUGCCAAGAGAGGCCACCAUCAUCCGGCACACAUCUGUGCGGGGCCUCAAGCGGCAGUCAGACGAGAGGAAGCGAGACCGGGAGCUGGGGCAGUGUGUGAAUGGGGAUUCCAGGGUGGAGCUGCGGUCGUAUGUCAGUGAGCCUGAGCUGGCGACCCUCAGCGGGGACAUGGCCCAGCCCUCCCUAGGACUUGUGGGCCCUGAGAGCAGGUACCAGACGCUGCCAGGCAGAGGGCUCUCAGGGUCCACGUCAAGGCUCCAGCAGUCGUCCACCAUUGCUCCCUACGUCACACUCCGGAGGGGUCUCAAUGCCGAAAGCAGCAAGGCGACCUUCCCUAGACCUAAGAGUGCCUUGGAGCGCCUGUACUCAGGGGAUCACCAGCGAGGCAAGAUGAGUGCAGAGGAGCAGCUGGAGCGCAUGAAGCGACACCAGAAGGCCCUGGUCCGAGAGCGCAAGAGGACACUGGGCCAAGGGGAGAGGACGGGCCUGCCCUCAUCUCGCUACCUCAGCCGGCCGCUCCCUGGAGAUCUUGGCUCAUGGAAGCGUGAGCAGGACUUUGACCUGCAGUUGCUGGAACGGGUCGUGCAAGGGGAAAAAAAGGACAAGGAGGAGAAUGGCUGGUUGAAAGUGCAGGCCAUGCCUGUCACUGAGUUGGACCUGGAGCCUCAAGACUAUGACUUGGACAUCAGCAGAGAGCUGUCCAAACCAGAGAAGGUGUCAAUCCCUGAGCGCUACGUGGAGCUAGAUCCCGAAGAGCCACCCAGCCUUGAGGAGCUGCAGGCGCGGUACCGCAAAGCCGAGAAGAUCCGCAACAUCCUCGCCCGGUCAAGCAUGUGCAACCUACAGCCGACCUCAGGCCAGGACCAGAACAGUGUGGCUGACCUGGACUUGCAGCUGCAGGAGCAGGAGCGCAUCAUCAACAUCUCCUACGCCCUGGCCUCCGAGGCCUCCCAGCGUAGCAAGCAGGUGGCAGCACAGCAGCUGGCCCUCCUCCCGCCUAAAGGCCCCCUGUCUUCCAGGACGGUGCCACCUUACCCCCCUUUUACCAACGGACUCCACUACACCUUUGUCUAACACCUUCCAA